GCACACCUCUCACCUCCCGUGGUGUGAUCUGGUUCCUAACAGGUAACAGACCGGUACUGGUCCAUGGCGCGGGAGUUGGGGACCUCUGCCCUAUGGGAUCCUCCAUUCCUUUCUCCUUUCCUCUCUGGCUUGAGAAAACCACAGUCCUAAAUUUUUUAUUAUUGCUUUGCUUUUCUUUAUAAUUUAAUUCCUAAGUGAUAUUUUAGUUUUGUGUGCUUUUGUACUUCAUUAAGUAGAAUUAUACUUAUUCUUCUGCAACUUGCAUUUUUCACUCGAUAUCUUAUUUCCAAGUUUUAUCCAUGUGGUGUGUAUAGUGAUAGUUCAUUCAUUUUGCUAUUGUCCAGUCUUUAUCAUGGAAAUGCACCACAGUAUGCUUAUGUAUUGUCCUGUUUAUGAACUUUUGUGUGACUUACAGUUUGUUGACACUAUGAAAGCUUUUAUUAAUGGCGUCUGAUGUGCAUGUAUAACAUCUAAUGCUCAUGUAGGUUGUCUCAGGUCUAUACACAGUGGAAUUGCUAGGUUAUAGGGUAUGUGAAUGUCCAAUUUUAAUAUACAAUGUAGACCAUGCUAAAUCAUUUUCCAAUUAUUUUUAUCUAUUUAUAUUCUUGCCAGCAGUAUAUGAGAGCUUCUAUCUUUGCACAGUCACCAACAUUUAGUAAUGUCAGACUUGUAAAUUUUUGCUAAUCUACUGAGCGUGAACUAAUUUAAUUUGUAUUUCCCUGAGCAUCAGUGAAGUCAAGCAUGUUUGCUUCAGUGAAGUCAAGCAUGCUUUCCUGGGUUUAUUAACAUUUGUGAUUUCUGUCUAUAAAUCAUCUGUUCAGGUCUUUUGACCCAUAUUUCUAUUGGAUUAUUUCUGGUUUUAAAGUGGGUCUGUAGGAAUUCUGUAUAUAUCGGGAACAAAUCUUUUUAGUUAUAUAUGUGAGAGAUAUCUUCUUCCAAUUAGUGGCUUGUCUUUUCAUUUUCCAUAUAGCGUCUUUGAUAAAGAGCCAUUAUUAAUCUUGUUCGUCCGUUUUUCAUGGUUUGCCUUUUUGUGUCUUAAGAAGUCCCUUCCUAACCAGAGGUUCAUAAACACAAACUUCUAGAUUGUCUUCUAAAAUGUUUAUAGUUUUGUCCCUGUGAAUGGUUUAAAGGUGUCCAAUGUGUUUUUUCUAUAGAGAUAACUGUUCUAGGACAAUCUAUUAAAAACUCUUCUGUUGUAGGACUUUCUCCUUAGUUCAGCUAAAAACGGGUCCUUGUCACACGACCAUGAAAGAUUAGGCUUGCAGACACUUUGAAGGGUGAGAAAAAUGGAAUUUAUUGGGUGAAAAGGAAAAAAACUCAGCAAAGCAAGAGAGCUUCCUGUUAACAGAUCCCCAUCUCACAGAUAGAAUUCCCAGUUACCACCCCGGAAAAAGAAAGGACAGACUCCUACCCCCUAAAACCGGCAGAAACUUCCAUGGCUCAACCUGUUCUCCCAGUGCUCAGGCCGGUGGGAGUUUCUCCAGGGACCCCUUUGUAUUUGAAUGUUUCAUUUUCUUUCCCUACAGAGGUGUAAAUGCCAGCUGACUGGAAUCAUGUCAUAGAUGAAGUUUCUCUCUGAGUGUGGACCUGUUUCCUGGGUUCCCUGGAGAACACAGGCAUUUGAGUCAGCCAGAUGUUGAGGGGCCCUACCAGGGAACUUCUUUAUAUUUUAAAUAAGAAGUCAUUUAUCUCACAUAACAAGUUAGAAGCUAUUCUGGGUUAACCCAAGGCACAAUGAUGGCAUCAAGAACCCCGGCUCUUCCCAUAUUUUCCUCUGCCAGAGUCAGUUUGUCAGUGAUGAUUCCUCACAGCUCCAACUGCUUCGAGCCACAUCUGCAGUGGAAAAAAGGCUUCAUAUUUUAAAUUCUAACCUCAAGGUUGUUGUGGACGACCCAGGUGGUGUGCAUUCAAGUUGCAAGCUGCUUUCCCAUGCAGUCCCACUCAGGGUCACGAGUUCUCAGGGGAGGAUUUUUUUCUCUGUCCAUUCAGUCCUGAGUUUCAAGAUGGGCAACUUGCCUUUCAGAUCCCUGUGUAAAGAAUGAAGGUAUUUAUUUCUAGUUCACCUGACUCUCAGGGUGCAGCCCUUGGGGCCUACAAUUUACACAGGAAUCUCACAUUAAACCCCUCUCCAUGGGCGGGCCUUGGGCUUUGUCCUCUGCCCUUACGCCUCAUGAGACAGUGAAGAGCUAAGCUGGAAUUCACCAAGGUUUGUUGGAGACUGAACCGUUGCAAGGAACAGACGAAGAUGCAGUAGCCAGUGCUGACUUCUCUAGCAUGCUCUCUGAGGAGGAAAAGGAAGAGUUAAAAGCAGAGUUAGUUCAGCUAGAAGACGAAAUUACAACACUACGACAAGUUUUGUCAGCGAAAGAAAGGCAUCUAGUUGAGAUAAAACAAAAACUCGGCAUGAACCUGAUGAAUGAAUUAAAACAGAACUUCAGCAAAAGCUGGCAUGACAUGCAGACUACCACUGCCUACAAGAAAACACAUGAAACCCUGAGUCACGCAGGGCAAAAGGCAACUGCAGCUUUCAGCAACGUUGGAACGGCCAUCAGCAAGAAGUUCGGAGACAUGAGUUACUCCAUUCGCCAUUCCAUAAGUAUGCCUGCUAUGAGGAAUUCUCCUACUUUCAAAUCAUUUGAGGAGAGGGUUGAGACAACUGUCACAAGCCUCAAGACGAAAGUAGGCGGUACGAACCCUAAUGGAGGCAGUUUUGAGGAGGUCCUCAGCUCCACGGCCCAUGCCAGUGCCCAGAGCUUGGCAGGAGGCUCCCGGCGGACCAAGGAGGAGGAGCUGCAGUGCUAAGUCCAGCCAGCGUGCAGCUGCAUCCAGAAACCGGCCACUACCCAGCCCAUCUCUGCCUGUGCUUAUCCAGAUAAGAAGACCAAAAUCCCGCUGGGAAAAACCCAGGCCUUGACAUUGUUAUUCAAAUGGCCCCUCCAGAAAGUUUAAUGAUUUCCAUUUGUAUUUGUGUUGAUGAUGGACCACUUGACCAUCACAUUUCAGUAUUCAUAGAUGACUGUCACAUUUUAAAAUGUUCCCACUUGAGCAGGUACACAACUGGUCAUAAUUCCUGUCUGUGUAAUUCGAUGUAUAUUUUUCCAAACAUGUAGCUAUUGUUUGCUUUGAUUUUUGCUUGGCCUCCUUUAUGAUGUGCAUGUCCUUGAAGGCUGAAUGAACAGUCCCUUUCAGUUCAGCAGAUCAACAGGAUGGAGCUCUUCAUGACUGUCUCCAGCAAUAGGAUGAUUUACUAUAAAUUUCAUCCAACUACUUGUGAUCUCUCUCACCUACAUCAAUUAUGUAUGUUAAUUUCAGCAAUUAAAAGAAUUGAUUUUAAUGACUUUGAAUUCUUAAUUUCUUUGUCUUAAAAGUUGCUAGUUAUGAUUUUACAGAUGCAAUUUUAAAUCAACUUUUAGCCAGGUGCGGCGGCUCACACCUGUAAUCCCAACUAUUUUGGAUGCCAAGGUGAGAGGAUUGCUUGAGGCCAGGAGUUAAAGAUCAGCCUGGGCAACACAGACCCUGUCUCUACAAAAAAAGAAAAAAAUUAGCCAGACAUAGUGUUGCUUGCCUGUAGUCCCAGCUACUCUAGAGGCUGAGGCAGGAGGAUUGCAUGAGCCUAGGAGUUCGAAACUGCAGUGAGCUAUGAUUGCACCACUGCACUACUCCAGCCUGGGUGACAGAGUGGGACACUGUCUCCAAAAAUAGUAAUAAUAAGUAGUCAACUUUUACUGCUAAUUUGGUGAACAUGAGAGAGGAUAUGAAAAUAAAUAUUACCUCAGCUAUCCUAGGAUGUUAAAAUAAUCUCCAAUUUUAAAAUUCUCUCCAAUCUACAUACAGUAGUAGUUAGUCAGAUAAAGGAUAUCCAAAAAAGAGAUAGCUAGAAAAUGGGAGAAGCAGAGUUCUGCAACCCCUUUCAGUUUGUAAAUUGUUCACAUGUAUGAAAAUAACUGGUAUUUAUCAAUCCACUCAGAUUUCUGCACUAACUUUUAUCUUAUAUAUCAUAUGUAUCUCUUUUCUUUUUCUAAAUGGGAACAUAUAUUUGUUAUUAGGUGGCAGAGAUAUAGCCUUAAGAUAUAUUUGUAAAAUGCACACUGAAUAGACAUCCAACCUAAAAAAAAUCACUAUUUAAAAAGCCCAUAUAAUAUAUACAUAUUUGUUAGCAUGCUAAUUGUUCAUGUUUUGUGUUUAUUAAAUAGAAGUGAUAUAUAUGACAUUUUGAAGUAAAGCACAUCUGAAAAAUUCUACUCAAA